AGCCUCACUGUCCUGUCUUGAACAUCCUCCACCAAAGUGUGAACACAGGUGGCAUGGGCUUCGUAACGAAUAAGAGCGCCUUCAAAGCAGGAGAUUCCCUGUACCUGCGAAGGGCCUUCGUGAACAACCUUGGAGAGGAAAGGAGAACCAGGAUUCAGAUCCAAAGCAUCCAGAAGGCUUUAGACAUCCAGAUCAGGGAGAUUGAUAGAGAAAAAGCAGCCCUGAAGAGAUUUUUGGUAAAGCUUCACAAGACAACUGGCUAUUUUCCUCAAAAGCCAUUGUGGUGACUGAUGCUGUGCCACCAUAGGGGACGAGUUCAUCUGAAACAUCCAAUACAGACAGAACACACCUGGGUCUCCUUCUGUAUCUCUCUGUGACCCAAGAAAGCAGUAGAAGUGGCUACUGGGACAAGCCAAAAAAGAAAAAAAAGGACUAGAUAAUUGAGGACACAAAUGGACUGCCUCUAAAAUAAUAAACAAAACCUCCUACAAAAGAGAGAAUAAUGCGCUGAUUUUUUUCCCAGCUGAUUCUAUUUCUUUACAACUUGAGGUGGUAAUAUGCAGUGCACGUGUUAUUUUCUUACAGAUUCUCCUGGAGGCAAGAAUAAAGCUGAGCUAUUUUAGAGAUCUUUCAGAUACUGAUCAUGAAAUACAUAUUAUAUUUGCCUUAA